GCGCCGGACCGGAAAGCCGGGGAAGUGGCCGAGGAGGGAGGGCUGCGAGCCAUGGCGACCAAGACGGCGGGCGUGGGGCGGUGGGAGGUAGUGAAGAAGGGUCGGCGGCCUGGGGUCGGCGCCGGCGCCGGCGGCCGAGGAGGCGGCAGGAACCGCAGGGCGCUCGGGGAAGCAAACGGAGUGUGGAAAUACGACCUGACCCCUGCAAUCCAGACCACAAGCACCCUUUAUGAGCGGGGCUUUGAGAAUAUCAUGAAGCGGCAGAAUAAGGAGCAGGUCCCACCCCCUGCUGUGGAACCUAAGAAACCAGGGAACAAGAAGCAGCCAAAGAAGGUGGCAACUCCUCCCAACCAAAACCAGAAGCAGGGCCGCUUCCGCAGCCUGGAGGAAGCACUGAAAGCUCUGGAUGUGGCAGACCUGCAGAAGGAACUGGACAAGAGCCAGAGUGUGUUCUCUGGAAACCCAUCCAUAUGGUUGAAGGACCUGGCCAGCUAUCUCAACUACAAGCUACAAGCUCCUCUAAGUGAACCCACGCUGAGCCAGCAUACUCAUGAUUAUCCCUACAGCCUGGUGAGCCGGGAGCUACGUGGGAUCAUCCGAGGGCUGCUGGCGAAGGCAGCAGGGUCUCUGGAGCUCUUUUUUGACCACUGUCUGUUCACCAUGUUGCAAGAGCUGGAUAAGACACCAGGGGAGUCACUACAUGGUUACCGCAUCUGUAUCCAGGCCAUCCUGCAAGACAAGCCCAAGAUUGCCACGGCAAACCUAGGCAAGUUCCUGGAACUGCUGAGGUCCCACCAGAGCCGACCAGCAAAGUGUCUCACCAUCAUGUGGGCCCUGGGUCAAGCAGGUUUUGCCAACCUCACCGAGGGACUGAAAGUGUGGCUGGGGAUCAUGCUGCCUGUGCUGGGCAUCAAGUCUCUGUCUCCCUUUGCCAUCACAUACCUGGAUCGGCUGCUCCUGAUGCAUCCCAACCUUACCAAGGGCUUCGGCAUGAUUGGCCCCAAGGACUUCUUCCCACUUCUGGACUUUGCCUAUAUGCCGAACAACUCCCUGACACCCAGCCUGCAGGAGCAGCUGUGUCAGCUCUACCCCCGACUGAAAGUGCUGGCAUUUGGAGCAAAGCCGGAUUCCACCCUGCAUACCUACUUCCCUUCUUUCCUGUCCAGAGCCACCCCUAGCUGUCCCCCUGAGAUGAAGAAAGAGCUCCCUGUUGACAGCUGCCUGCCCCGCUCACUCGAGCUUCACCCUCAGAAGAUGGAUCCCAAGAGACAGCACAUUCAGGGUGGAUGUGCGGCCUGGAUGGCCUUGCUUACGGGAAGGGGAUCACCUCUUAGCACUCCCCGCCUCUGCCAGCCCCAUGCCCCCAGCAGCCUCUCCCUCUGUCGUGCUGUGCAGCUCCUGAGCAGCCUGACUGAGUGCCUGACGGUGGACCCCCUCAGUGCCAGCGUCUGGAGGCAGCUGUACCCUAAGCACCUGUCACAGUCCAGCCUUCUGCUGGAGCACUUGCUCAGCUCCUGGGAGCAGAUUCCCAAGAAGGUACAGAAGUCUUUGCAAGAAACCAUUCAGUCCCUCAAGCUUACCAACCAGGAGCUGCUGAGGAAGGGUAGCAGUAACAACCAGGAUGUCGUCACCUGUGACAUGGCCUGCAAGGGCCUGUUGCAGCAGGUUCAGGGUCCUCGGCUGCCCUGGACGCGGCUCCUCCUGUUGCUGCUGGUCUUCGCUGUAGGCUUCCUGUGCCAUGACCUCCGGUCACACAGCUCCUUCCAGGCCUCCCUUACUGGCCGGUUGCUUCGAUCAUCUGGCUUCUUACCUGCUAGCCAACAAGCGUGUGCCAAGCUCUACUCCUACAGUCUGCAAGGCUACAGCUGGCUGGGGGAGACACUGCCGCUCUGGGGCUCCCACCUGCUCACCGUGGUGCGGCCCAGCUUGCAGCUGGCCUGGGCUCACACCAAUGCCACAGUCAGCUUCCUUUCUGCCCACUGUGCCUCUCACCUUGCGUGGUUUGGUGACAGUCUCACCAGUCUCUCUCAGAGGCUACAGAUCCAGCUCCCCGAUUCCGUGAAUCAGCUACUCCGCUAUCUGAGAGAGCUGCCCCUGCUUUUCCACCAGAAUGUGCUGCUGCCACUGUGGCACCUCUUGCUUGAGGCCCUGGCCUGGGCCCAGGAGCACUGCCAUGAGGCAUGCAGAGGUGAGGUGACCUGGGACUGCAUGAAGACACAGCUCAGUGAGGCUGUCCACUGGACCUGGCUUUGCCUACAGGACAUUACAGUGGCUUUCUUGGACUGGGCACUUGCCCUGAUAUCCCAGCAGUAGGCCCUGCCUUCCUGGCCACUGAUUUCUGCAUGGGUAGACCAUCCAAGACUGCAGCGGGUAGAAGGUGGCAGUUCUUCAUGGGAGUCUUUUUAACUUGGUGCCUGAGUUCUCUCCUAGGCAAGUGGCCAGUUGCCUCCACCUCAGUUCUUCCAUCUUUGGUGGGGACAGGGCCCAGCAGCAUCUCAGCCUCCUACCCACAAUUCCACUGAACACUUUUCUGGCCCUACUGCACAUGGCCCCCAGCCUCCAUCCUUGUGCUGGUAGCCUCUCACAACUCCGCCCUUGCCCUCUGCCUUCCACUUCCUUCCAUCUCAUUUCUAAACCCCAAACAGCUCAUCUCUAAAAAGAUAGAACUCCCAGCAGGUGGCUUCUGUGUUCUUCUGACAAAUGAUUCCUGCUUCUCCAGACUUUAGCAGCCUCCUGUUCCCAUUCUUGGUCACAGCUCUAGCCACAGCAGAAGGAAAGGGGCUUCCAGAAGAAUAUAGCACCGCAUUGGGAAACAGCAGCCUCACCUCCACCUGAAGCCUGGGUGUGGCUGUCAGUGGACAUGGGGAGCUGGAUGGAAAUGCCUCUCACUUCAAAAUGCCCAGCCUGCCCCAAAUGCCUCUAAGCCCCUCCCUGUCCCCUCCCUUGUAGUCCUACUUCUUCCAACUUUCCAUUCCCCAUCAUGCUGGGGGUCUUGGUCACAAGGCUCAGCUUCUCUCCACUGUCCAUCCCUCCUAUCAUCUGUAGAGCAGAGCACAGGCAGUUGUGUGCCUUGGGCCCAGGGAACCCUCCAUCAACCUGAGACAGGACUCAGUAUAUGGUUCUUGGGUAUGCCCUACCAGGUGGAAUAAAGGACACAGAUUUGAUUUCUA